AGACUUCUGCUGGCAGUUACUGAGAGAGAUAGGCUUUCCAUCCAUGGCAGCCAUUUACUUUUGCUCUGGGAGACGUUUGUAAUAGAAAAGGCACAACUGGGGUAUUUAUUCAUUUCCCCCCGUUCCUCUAGUGUUUGGUGGCGUUGCCGUUGCAAGUGCGCAGGGCUAAAAUGAACUGGUUAUCUUAGGAUCAUGGAAAACCUGGAAUCAAGGCUCAAGAAUGCCCCCUAUUUUCGUUGUGAGAAGGGAACCGAUUCCAUCCCUCUAUGCCGGAAGUGUGAGACGCGUGUCUUAGCCUGGAAGAUCUUCUCUACCAAAGAGUGGUUCUGCAGGAUCAAUGACAUAUCACAGAGGAGGUUUCUAGUUGGCAUUCUGAAGCAGUUAAAUAGCUUAUAUUUGUUACACUAUUUCCAAAAUAUCCUUCAGACCACACAGGGAAAGGAUUUCAUCUAUAACAGGUCCCGGAUCGACCUCAGCAAGAAAGAGGGGAAAGUUGUGAAGUCCUCCUUGAACCAAAUGUUGGAUAAAACAGUAGAACAGAAGAUGAAAGAGAUCUUGUAUUGGUUUGCGAACAGCACCCAGUGGACCAAGGCGAAUUAUACUCUCUUACUGCUGCAGAUGUGCAACCCCAAAUUACUGCUCACUGCUGCCAAUGUGAUCAGAGUCCUGUUUCUGAGAGAGGAGAACAAUAUCUCAGGGCUCAAUCAAGACAUCACAGAUGUGUGUUUUUCCCCUGAGAAAGACCACAGCUCCAAGUCUGCGACCUCACAAGUCUAUUGGACAGCCAAAACUCAGCACACAUCCCUUCCUUUGUCCAAAGCCCCAGAAAAUGAACACUUCCUUGGGGCAGCAUCUAACCCUGAGGAACCAUGGAGGAAUUCACUCCGGUGUAUAUCCGAAAUGAAUAGGCUGUUUUCUGGAAAAGCAGACAUAACCAAGCCAGGGUACGAUCCCUGCAAUCUAUUGGUUGACCUGGAUGACAUCAGAGACCUGUCUUCUGGGUUCAGCAAAUACCGAGACUUCAUCCGUUACCUGCCCAUCCACCUCUCCAAGUACAUUCUAAGAAUGCUGGAUAGACACACCCUGAACAAGUGCGCCUCUGUGAGCCAGCACUGGGCCGCCAUGGCUCAACAGGUCAAGAUGGACUUGUCAGCGCACGGCUUCAUUCAGAACCAGAUUACCUUCUUGCAGGGGUCCUAUACAAGAGGAAUUGAUCCUAAUUAUGCCAAUAAGGUUUCUAUCCCAGUUCCUAAAAUGGUAGAUGACGGGAAGAGCAUGCGUGUGAAACAUCCGAAGUGGAAGUUGAGAACGAAGAAUGAGUACAACCUGUGGACUGCAUACCAGAACGAGGAAACGCAGCAGGUCCUGAUGGAGGAGAGAAAUGUUUUCUGUGGGACCUACAAUGUUCGCAUUCUCUCUGACACGUGGGAUCAAAACCGAGUCAUCCACUAUUCCGGGGGAGAUCUGAUAGCUGUGUCAUCUAAUCGAAAGAUCCAUCUUCUGGACAUCAUACAAGUGAAAGCGAUACCCGUUGAAUUCCGAGGCCAUGCUGGGAGUGUCCGGGCCCUCUUCCUGUGUGAGGAGGAAAACUUUCUCCUAAGCGGGAGCUAUGACCUAAGUAUCAGAUACUGGGAUCUGAAAAGUGGGGUUUGCACACGAAUCUUCGGUGGUCACCAGGGGACUAUCACUUGCAUGGACUUGUGUAAGAACAGGCUCGUAUCUGGAGGAAGAGAUUGCCAGGUAAAAGUAUGGGAUGUAGACACAGGGAAGUGCCUGAAGACGUUUAGACACAAAGACCCCAUCUUGGCCACCAGGAUCAAUGAUACCUACAUUGUGAGCAGCUGUGAGCGAGGGCUGGUGAAAGUGUGGCACAUUGCCAUGGCCCAGUUGGUAAAGACUCUCAGUGGCCACGAGGGAGCUGUGAAAUGCCUGUUCUUUGACCAGUGGCAUCUCCUCUCAGGAAGCACUGAUGGCCUGGUCAUGGCCUGGAGCAUGGUGGGGAAGUACGAGCGCUGCCUGAUGGCCUUCAAGCAUCCCAAAGAGGUGCUCGACGUGUCCCUUCUCUUCCUCCGGGUCAUCAGCGCCUGUGCAGAUGGCAAGAUCCGAAUUUACAAUUUCUUCAAUGGGAACUGUAUGAAGGUGAUAAAAGCCAAUGGCAGAGGCGAUCCUGUGCUGUCCUUCUUUAUUCAGGGCAACAGAAUUUCAGUCUGCCACAUCAGCACAUUUGCUAAAAGAAUUAACGUGGGAUGGAAUGGAAUCGAACCAAGUGCUACAGCUCAGGGAGGAAAUGCCUCCUUGACCGAGUGUGCUCAUGUGAGACUCCACAUCGCAGGACACUUACCAGCAUCGAGGCUGCCCGUGGCCGCUGUCCAGCCCAUGACAGGCGGGAUGGCCCCAACCACAGCUCCGACCCAUGUGUUGGCAAUGCUGAUCCUUUUCAGUGGUGUGUAGCAGCAGGUAUACAGGAAAAUGUUGAAGAGCCCCAGGGCUCCUGUGAGUGGAUUCACCCCCAAGGUCAGAAUGGCAACUCCUGGAACAGCACAACAAGUGGCAAAGGACACAGCUAGCAACGGGCUGGAAAAAGGCAGAGAACGUGGAGUGAUCAUCUCCAACUCAACUCAAUCACACUGCCUAAAAUCGGCACUGACAAAGUACAAAUAAUCCACCUAUCCAGUAGAGGCAGCACUGAUCUGGCUGAUUCCUGGAUAUGGGGAAUCCUCUUUAUGAAACAAACUUACAAUAAGAAAGAAUAUGUUUGUGGGAGCUCUGGCUGCUCUUCUUGAUUUUGCUAGCUAAGAGUAAAGUGGUUAAGAGAGUCAGGAUUAGAGUGUUCUGGAUUCAUAUAGGUUCUGUCCCUUCCUGGCUAUAGGGCAGCUAGGUUUCACUUACUCCUCUCUAUAAGAGAAAUGAUCAUCUUUUCCUCCUAGGGUUGAAGACUGACUGAGACAAUGCCUCCUGCACAGUGUUCCAUUUUAUAUUUAGUCAUGAACAAACAACUUCAGACACAAUAUUGGAAGAUUUGGGCAGAAAAUACUACCUGAAUUCUGGAAGCUGUUCUUCCCCUGUAUUUAUACUUUAUUAAGACGUCACUUAAUUAGUGAUCAUGAGUAGCAAUGAUGUGCCUCUGACUGCCAUCAUUACAAUGUCUGUAAUGAAUUACAGGCUCAGCAUGCUACCGGUUCCCGACAACAGUAAACACCAGGUGGCCGUUGUGUAGUACCAGUGCCGUAACGUGACUUAUGGACACGGGAUUUUCAAGGGGAGGUCGCACAGUGUUAUUUAUGCAAAUGAAACCCAUCAUCUAAAACUCUACAAUGAUAAUGAUUAUUAUAAGCCUGUUUCUCAAAAGAGCCAACUUCUAAAAGUAGACUUUGUAUGGAAUCUUGUGAAAGGCUUUUUGAGAGUCUAGAUAAAUUGGAUCUACUAGUUCCUGCUUAUAUGCAUGUUUAUUUAUUCUUUCUUGAGAAACCUAAGGAGGUUACUCAAGCCUGCCUUCUCCUAGCAGAAGCCAUAAUUCCACUUCUGAGUAAGGUAUGUUUGUGUAGUGUUCAGUGACCCUGCUGGAUUACAGAUUCCACAACACGUUUCUUAGCAAGCAAGAGUCACCAGUGUGCAGCUUCUAGGGUGCUCUGGUUUUAAAAACAGCCAACUCCCUAGAGAGGCAGACUUUACCCUAUGUGCACACAUGUGAGAUGAUACCCUUCUAUGCACAGGGUUGCAGUGUUCCUAUGGCAGGAGAGAGGGCCUGUAUCUAUGAGAGGGCCCUUCUAGGAAAAAGACUAACUUGUAGAAUUAUGACGAGUUAGAAUUUAGCCGGGAGGGGGCCAGAGGAGAGCCCAGCAGCUGGAACUACAGUACGGAAUGAAGUCAGGGCAACAGAAUAUGAAAGCUAGAAGUGACUUGAUGGAGAAUUCUGGCCACCACUCUACCACUCUGCUAUAGGGGCCAGCACUGACUCUUUCCUACCUGGCCUGCAGCCUCUGUGCCCAAAGAGUGACCCAACAGAAUGGAAUUUUGAUGGAAAAUGAGAAAAUAUAAGGGAUAUGUUGCUGUCAAGGUGCCUGUGACAGAAGAACUAUAAAUUACAGCUGAGAGACUUCUGAGUGCACAUUCUGCCUUGAGGUGGCAUUUCCACCCACCUGUUCCUGGGCCAUCUCUUCUGAACCCUGUGGUCAGUUACUUCCACAAUACUCACUCAGGCACCCUCAAUAAUCCAUUCUGCCUUGUCCAUCCAACAUUCCCACUCUGGAUCUGCUCAAUAACCUACUGUCUCUGCUCCUGCUGGGAAAGGCUUACACUUAUACUAACUGGCCCCAUUUCAAGGGGAUGGUUUAACAGUGCGGGUGCUUAGCCAGGGCUGAUUUCCACUUUCGUUCCUUAUAGUGACUAUUUUAACUCUUCUCCUGCCUUCUCAAGGCUCCAGGUUCACUCUAGCUCCCAAGACGCCUUAACAGAUGCCCUUCCCUCUUAUACAACAGUGACAAAUGCCCUCAGAUUUACUUCCUUCCUCCCAUUUCAGAAGAGGCUGUCUUCAUUCCUUUUAAAGAUAAACCCUCCACUUUUGUUUUUAUUUAAUCUCCUCCCUAAUCUCUAUUCUAUCCCUUCUAUCUCUACUGUCUAUUAACCUCCUGCAUCAAAUAAAUUACUUUCUUCAUAUUUCCCCCAAGGUAAUACCCCUCUUGCUUCAACACUCUUCAAAGCCAAGCAUCCUGAUGGAGUGGAUCACACACAUUCCUUGCCUUUCUCUCUUCCAUCCCUCUGUUUCCUAUUUGUUCCUCAACUGUAUCCCUCACCAGCUGCUGAAACACAUUUCUCUAAGGUGGAGGUAUACAAGGGGACUUGAAAAAGUUCAUGGAAAAUGCAUAUUAUGAAAAGACUAUGCAUGGAUUUCAAAAAUUUUUUGUACCAAAAUAAACUCAUACUAACUUGUUAUAACAUGUCUGAACAGGAUCUAGAUUGAGGCAUUAAGGAGGAUAAGACAUCAGUUUGAAAAGAGCCCUUAUCAAAGCAACAUGAAUUCUGCUAAAACAGAAGCAAGAACAAAUAUCAAAUUUAUGCUAACGCUUGGAUGGAAGAAUAGUGAAAUCAUUGAUGCUUUACAAGAAGUUUAUGGGGACAAUGCCCCCCCAAAUCAGCAGUUUACAAAUGGAUAACUUGUUUAAGAACAGAUGAUGUUGAAGAUUAAAGUCCACAGCUGCAAACCAUCCACAUCAAUUUGUGAGGAAAAAAUGAAUCUUUUUCAUGCCCUAAUUUAAGUGGACCAAUGGUUAACGGUAGAAACAACAACCAAUACCAUAGACGUCUCAAUUGGUUUAGCUCACACAAUUCUGAUUGAAAAAUUAAAGUUGAGCUAACUUUCCACUCAGUGGGUGCCAAAACCAUUGUACUCAGAUUGGCUGCAGACAAGAGCAGGGCUUUCAAUGGAAAUUUUCAACAAAUGGGAUCAAGAUCCUGAGGCAUUUCUUCAAAAAAAAAAAAAAAAGAAGAAAAUGAAUAUAUAACAGGAGGUGAAAUAUGGCUUUACCACUACAAUCCUGAACACAAAGACAAUCAAAGCAGUGGCUACCAAGAGGUGGGAGUGGUCCAGUCAAAGAAAAAGCGGACAGAUCAAGAGCAAAGCUCAUGGCCAUAGUUUUUUGGGAUGCUGAAGGCAUUUUGCUUGAUUCCUUUCCAGAAGGCUAAAGAACAAUAACAUCUACUUAUUAUGAGAGUGUUUUGAAAAAAAUUAGCAAAGCUUUAGCAGAAAGCUUCCCCAGAGAGUUCUUCUCCACCACAACAAUGCUCCUGCUCAUUCCUCUCAUCAAACACGGGCAACCUUGUGAGCAUUUGGAUGGGAAAUCAUUAGGCAUCCACUUCACAGUCCUGAUUUGGCUCCUUCUGCCGUCUUUUUGUUUCCUAAUCUUAAAAAGUCUUUAAAGGGAAUCCAUUUCUCUUCAGUUAAUAAUGUAAAAAAGAAUGCUUUGACAUGGUUAAAUUCCCAGGACUCUGUGAGUUCUUUACAGAUAGACUAAAUGGCUGGUAUCACUGCUUACCAAAGUGUCUUGACCUUGAUGGAGAUUAGGUUGAGAAAUAGGUUUUUUUAAAAAAUUUUAUCUUUUAAUUCUAUUUUUUCCAUAAUCUUUUUGAAGUUCCCUCAUACGUCAUAUGACCUGGAACCAUCUAUUUUCCCAACAUGGCACACAAUAUGAUUUUCCAGAUGAAAGAUUACAAAGAUACCUCUGUGUUGUUACAUCUCCUAUAUACCCAGAAAGGAAACUUUAGAUGGCUAAAAAGCAGUGCACAUAUUAUAAUGUUGUUCUUCUUCCAAUAAGGUAAUUUAUAGCUUAUAAGAACAGAUUUUUUUUUUCCCUAUGAGACUCUAAAAAACUAGCUUUAUUUUGGGAGGGAGAAAAAUGUGGCUGAUAAACAUUUUAUUUUUCCUGAAUUGGCCCUUGUGUCAAAAAAAAAAAAAAAAAAAGAAGAAGAAGGUUGUUUACUCCUUCUUCAAGUUCUGUGGAGGCCAGUUGGAUUCAAAGAUAUUAGUGUUAUGAAAAGCCCUUUUAGAAGAGCACACAUGAAUUUAAUUUAUUGAGAUAGGCCAUUUUAUGUGUAAGUUUAGUUUCUGACCUUUGUUGAAGUCACAGAAAAUGAUGUGGCUCAAUUUUGGUGUUUAAAUCAAUGUGCACAAGGGCAUGAAUGAAAACUGGGUAGGCUGACAAGCCAUGCAAACGAAAAUGAAGCUAUUUACCCAGGAUGCCAUGAUCACUCUCAGCAUCCAGGCACCUGAAGGAAUCCUUCCCCUUCUGGCACGAGGAGCCCACAAUCAGUGGACUUCAGAGCUUUCUUGUGUUAUGGGCAAAGGUACUCCAAUUGCAAACUGUGUGAAAUUUAUUUUCCUGUUAUGUUUCAUUUUUCCUAAAACAUUUAUAACAAAAGUAAUAUACAUCCAAUUCAGAAAACUGGCAAUUCUAGAAAAUCACAAAGAAGAAAUUCUUCAUGAGUUAUUCGGAGAAACAUACUAGUUGAUAUCUUCUCAGCCUUUUUCCAAUGAUAUAACUACUUAAAAAAAAUUGAGAAUAUGCUAAAUUGUGGUUUUAUCCCCUGAUUUAUUUCAAUAUAUCUUAAUAAUUUCCCCAGGCUAUUAAAUAUAUUUUUUGCAUCAACAUCAUUAAUAUUUAUAACACACAGUGGCUUAUUCUUUGGAUACACCACAAUUAAUUCAACCAAUAUACUUUUUUUCAGACAUUCAGUCUUUUUCCAUUUUUAAAAAUCAAAAAGCGUGUUGGGAUAAAUAUCUUAUGGGUAGACUUUUGUUCACAGCUCUGGUUAGAAGAAAUUCCGAAGAUAAAUUCCUAGAUGUGAAACUGCUAAGUCAGAUGAUAUGCACAUGUUGUAGGGAUUUUGACACGUACUGUCAGGCUGUACUCCAGAGAGUUUGCACAAAUUUACACUCCCACCAGCACUAUAUGAGAGCACCAUCUUCUAGAACCUGUAUCAACACUGGCUGUGACAUUAAAAACAAAGCAAAACAAAAAAUAAAAUUUGCCAAUAGAUUAAAAAA